ACUUCUUGCUGCCUCACGGUUGCUGUUGCAGACCCAGGAGUCUCUGAAGGCUUCCGCGGCUUUGGGGCCGGUUGUGAGAUGCCAGGCAGAGGCCGCUGCCCGGACUGCGGCUCCACGGAGCUGGUGGAAGACUCGCACUAUUCGCAGAGCCAGCUGGUGUGCUCCGACUGCGGCUGCGUGGUCACCGAGGGGGUCCUUACCACUACCUUCAGCGACGAGGGCAAUCUCCGAGAGGUAACAUAUUCCCGAAGCACAGGGGAAAACGAACAAGUUAGUCGCAGCCAGCAACGAGGUCUCCGGCGAGUGAGAGACCUUUGUCGAGUUCUGCAGUUGCCACCAACAUUUGAGGAUACCGCGGUUGCCUACUACCAACAGGCAUAUCGGCACUCUGGCAUCCGAGCGGCCAGGCUGCAAAAGAAGGAGGUGUUGGUUGGGUGCUGCGUCUUAAUCACCUGCCGACAGCAUAACUGGCCCCUAACAAUGGGGGCCAUCUGCACGCUGUUGUAUGCAGAUUUGGAUGUGUUUUCUAGCACUUACAUGCAGAUAGUGAAGCUCCUGGGACUGGAUGUGCCAUCUCUGUGCUUGGCAGAACUGGUGAAGACCUAUUGCAGCAGCUUCAAACUGUUCCAAGCUUCACCUUCUGUGCCAGCCAAAUACGUGGAAGACAAAGAGAAGAUGCUGUCUCGAACAAUGCAGUUGGUGGAGCUGGCAAAUGAGACGUGGCUGGUGACCGGGAGGCAUCCCUUGCCCGUCAUCACUGCUGCGACUUUCCUGGCUUGGCAGUCGCUGCAGCCUGCAGAUCGGCUUUCAUGUUCCCUUGCCCGAUUUUGUAAAUUGGCAAAUGUGGACCUGCCCUACCCGGCGUCCUCCCGCCUGCAGGAGCUGCUGGCUGUGCUGCUGCGGAUGGCUGAGCAGCUGGCCUGGUUACGAGUUCUGAGACUUGACAAACGGUCUGUGGUGAAGCACAUCGGUGACCUUCUCCAGCACCGCCAGUCACUGGUCCGCUCUGCCUUUCGGGAUGGGACAGCAGAAGUGGAGACCCGAGAGAAGGAGCCACCGGGGUGGGGACAGGGGCAAGGAGAAGGGGAGGUGGGAAAUAAUUCCUUAGGUUUACCCCAGGGGAAGCGGCCGGCCAGUCCUGCCCUUCUCUUGCCACCCUGCAUGUUGAAGUCCCCGAAGCGGAUCUGCCCUGUACCCCCUGUCUCCACUGUCACUGGAGAUGAGAACAUUUCUGAUAGUGAAAUAGAACAGUAUUUGCGUACCCCUCAGGAAGUUAGGGACUUUCAGAGAGCCCAGGCUGCUAGACAGGCUGCCACGAGUGUCCCUAACCCUCCCUGAUGGAUAUCCACUGGGAGCACUUCAUCCUGUUCUGACAGCUUGAUAACAUUCCUGUUAUAACCAAGGAUGGAAGUGUACACCAGUCCGUAGGUAUUGCUUUUCUUGUUUGAAGGAACCAAGAGGGGCUCUGCCAUUAGUUGGACCCUGGGUCCUGGAGUAAAGUCAGGAGUGCAGGGAUGACUAUAGGUAGGAGAGAUUCCCAUCCCUUGGUGUGGGAGAGCAAGUUGCCUAUGUCCAUGUUCUGUGAGAUGGCUUUCCUCAUAGAUGGAUGGGAAAAUGUCAGGCUCUUUGCUGCUGGUUUGAAUUGGACACACUGCUGCGGCUCCUCCUGCAGGCCUGAGGGGGCUUCCCUCUGCUUGUGGAGUGGUUGGCAUUCCCAGCAGUAUCAACCCUCAGAGGAGCGGGAACUGGGGAAUUCUGGCCCUACGUGCAUUCACAGGCAAUGAUGGGUUUGUGUGUAUGGUGUCAUGAGAUCCUCUACCUCAUAACAAAAGGACAGUGGGUAGACUAAGGCAGUAGCUCAAAGGGCUUUGCAAAAUUUUAAUAUAUUAAAACAAGAGGCAUCUGCUAGAAAACAUUCUAUUGUAUAAAACCCGAGUUCUUAAAAACAUGUUUUCUUUGGCACUUUCAUUCCCUCCCUCCCCUUUCCCCAGCAUAUUGCAAAAAGCUCUCCAGUGCUAAGGCAUUGGCAGGGUGUGUAAACAGCAGCCAGCAUAUGUGGAAGAAUAAUACAAAGCUUUUUUUUUUCUUCUAAUAUGUCUGUGCAGCAAGCAUAAAUAACAGGACCCAUUCCAAGGAGUGUGUGUGGGUUUUCCCCCUCCCCUGUGUCCUCUGUCACCUUGGUGAUGAGGCCAGAGUGAUGUGAAGACUGGGAGGGAACCCUAGGUCAGACCUUGGUUUCCUGUUGUUCUUCCCAAGACCCAGGGUUCCCUCGGUUUCCAUUUGGUCCUGUAGUGAAAUGCUGGUGGUUGGUUUUAGGUUGGGGAAAAGACGGGUGCUGGUGUUUAAAAGGAGUAAAGGCAUAGGCCCCUCAUGACCUGCAGGGACCCCAGCCACUGCCUCUGGGCUUGGCUUGAGCUCCUGGGAGUCGGGAAGCUGGUUUGACAUUUUGUAGGUUUCUCUCUACUGUGGAGCUGGAGAUCAAAUGAUUGGGAUGGUUCUUCCUCUGGCCUUACGGAGGCAAGGAAGUGCUCUUCCUUAGUCCCGUGGUGUUGUAAGGCUG